ACAUUCGAAAAACUCACUGUCUUGGAAACCUACCUAGAACCUCCACCCUCUGACACCAUGGUUAACUCUUGUUGUGGCUCUGUCUGCUCUGACCAGGGCUGUGAUCAAGGCCUCUGCCAAGAGACCUGCUGCCGCCCCAGCUGCUGCCAGACCACCUGUUGCUGCCCCAGCUGUGUUGUAUCCAGCUGCUGCCGCCCAUCCUGCUCUCAGACUACCUGCUGCCAGACCACUUGCUGUCGCCCCAGCUGCUGCCACCCAGUCUGUUGUCAGACCACCUGCCGCCCCAGCUGUGGUGUGUCCAGCUGCUGCCGCCCACUCUGCUGUCAGACCACCUGCCACCCCAGCUGUGGUAUGUCCAGCUGCUGCCGUCCACUCUGUUGUCAGACCACCUGCCGCCCCAGCUGUGGUGUGUCCAGCUGCUGCCGUCCACUCUGCUGUCAGACCACCUGCUGCCGUGCAACUUGCUGCCGCCCCAGCUGCUGUGGAUCCUCUUGUUGAACCUCAUAUUGGACUAUCAACCAUGAGCCAGUCACCAUCCCAUGAUAUGAAAGUGUCAUUUAUAUCAACUUGUCCAUGUGUUAAAUGGCCAUCAGCUUUAUUAUCCUGUUAUUCCACUAAGUAACUGGUGAAAGGGCAUCCAUCUACAUUUAAUACCACUCAUUUUUCCCAUGGAUCUCUUCCCAGCAGCAUUCAGACCUCAGAUGCAUGAUGCAGUUAGACUAAGCCUCUAAGUUUCUGACUGUUAUGCUUGAUUUGACCUUCAAAAUUACAUAUUAACUGUUCUUCAAUAAAUAUUAUCUUAAUAUCAGUAA